CAAUCUUUAAGAAGCUGCUACAGCUAUAAUGUAAGGUUAAGAGUUUAUUCUUUCAAAGCAGGUCUCCUCAUCUCUUAAACGCUAUACAUAUGAAGUAGAUAAAAACUGGUUUCUUUUUUGGUAGCAUUUAGGAUCUACAAAAGUGAUCCUUCAAUUACUUGGAAUUUCAAAAAAUUGAGGUUACCUAGUAACAAUGCACCAGUAGAACACAAAAUACUCUGACUUUGUUUAGUCUGUGGGAAAAGAAAAAUCUUUAAACUGGAAAGAUUUUGUAGUCUUACAAAGAUUACAUUGGAAUUGGAAUUACUGUAGUUCGUUUUUCCCUCUAGGAGGGCAGCCAUUUCUCUAAAAGUUGUGUAAAAGUUAAGACUAGGAUUUCAAAAUGCAAGCAGAUGUUGAUGAAGCAUACGAAAUGGGCAACUCCGUUUCUAUUUCGGAGCCGCAGCGACUCCGACUUUGUGCCCCAACCCUGUAAAGGGCAAAACCUCAUCCCUUCGGUGUAAACUUUCAAGAGAAGUGGGGCAGCACACUUUAGGCGUUUCACCAAGAGGCUGGCGACAUGCUAGGUCAGGUUGUCCGGAGAAUCGGGGCUGAAUGGGAGAGAUCUUGAGGGCAAGAGCCUCAGAGACCUUCAGGCACCGAGCUCGUGAAGGUUUCCAAGUGCCCCUCUCUAGCUGCUCCCAGGGGGAAUUAGUGGUUGCUACAGUAGUUUAAGAGGGUCGUGGUUUUUCGCAACCCGGGCGGCGAGAUGGCGCUUUGGUGUAAGCGAGGUAAGGUGGGUGCACUGGGAUCUCCGCUCUCGGAGCCUCCAGCUGACUGCCACGCCGACUUGUGGCCAGACCUGCGACCUCCGCCCUCCCCCGCGGCGCCAGCCUCUGGAAUCUGGCGUCGCCCCCACCUCUCCAGUCGAAGUGGGAGUCCCUCUGUGCGGGGCCUCGCCGCCAUACCCAGGCCGAAUGGGGGUGGGGAGGGAAGCUGGCAGAGCUCGGCCUCAGGAUCCGCGCCCCUGUGGAAAGACCGCAGAGGGAAGCCGUUUCACCAGCCUCUCCCCUUCUGGGGUCUCGGGAAACACGCGGUAAUUACCGAAGAACCCCGCACUCUGUGAGAGGCGAGGCUGCGGGGCUGCCGGGACGGUUUGAGGACCGGGCUCGGCCGAGGAGACUCCAACCUUCACCCUCCCUGGCCCCCGGUCCCACUUCCCGCCGUCUCCCGGCGCCGCCACUUCAGGUGUCACUAGUUCCAGGCGUCUGCUGAAAGAUUUGGAACAGAAGAUGAUGGCCACUCCGAACCAGACCGCCUGUAAUGCAGAGUCACCAGUGGCCCUGGAGGAGGCCAAGACCUCUGGUGCCCCGGGGAGCCCCCAAACACCCCCUGAGCGUCAUGACUCUGGUGGUUCCCUGCCCCUGACACCGCGGAUGGAGAGCCACUCAGAGGAUGAAGAUCUUGCUGGGGCUGUCGGUGGCCUGGGCUGGAACAGUAGGAGUCCCCGGACCCAGAGCCCAGGGGGCUGCUCAGCGGAGGCUGUGCUGGCCCGGAAGAAACACCGUCGGCGGCCAUCGAAGCGCAAAAGGCACUGGCGACCCUACCUGGAGCUGAGCUGGGCUGAGAAACAACAGCGGGAUGAGAGGCAGAGCCAGAGGGCCUCCCGGGUCCGCGAAGAGAUGUUCGCCAAAGGCCAGCCCGUGGCCCCCUACAACACCACCCAGUUCCUGAUGAAUGACAGGGACCCGGAGGAGCCCAACUUGGAUGUGCCCCAUGGGAUCUCCCACCCAGGUUCCAGUGGGGAGAGUGAGGCCGGGGACAGUGAUGGGCGGGGCCGAGCGCACGGUGAGUUCCAGCGGAAGGACUUCUCUGAGACUUACGAACGCUUCCACACCGAGAGCCUGCAGGGCCGCAGCAAGCAGGAGCUGGUGCGAGACUACCUGGAGCUGGAGAAGCGGCUGUCGCAGGCGGAGGAGGAGACUAGGAGGCUGCAGCAGCUGCAGGCGUGCACCGGCCAGCAGUCCUGCCGCCAGGUGGAGGAGCUGGCUGCCGAGGUCCAGAGGCUCCGGACCGAAAACCAGCGGCUUCGUCAGGAGAACCAGAUGUGGAACCGAGAGGGCUGCCGCUGUGAUGAGGAGCCGGGUACCUAGGGGUGCCUCCCAGCCUGGUGGACCCAAGGAGAAGGUCCCAUUUCGUGCACACUCAGGCCAGCUGGGUCUCAAGGAGGCAGGUGGCAGAUGAAAACCACCGUCAACACCCUGUGCGCCCUGAGAACAGCUAAAUCGGUUCAGACUCCCACCUCACCGUUUCCAUAGUUGGCUCUUUUGUGUCAUCUUACCCUUUACAGAGAAAUUAAAUGGCCUUGGUGGGACCAAAUGGGA